AGACGCUGCUGAGGCGGCUUCGGUUGCGGGUCGGAACGGCGCUGCUCUGCGGGGCCGGUCCAGGCUGGCAGCUGCCGGCGCUUGGCGGUGAGGGCGGGCUCCCGAGUGGCCCCCCACCGAAGGCGGUGGGACCAGCGGCUGAGGCCAGGAUGCCGUCCAGGCGGCGCGGCGGCUCCUCACUCAUCCCAGGUAAGGGGGACGCGGCGCUCGCUGCGGCUCCGCUCCCCUCUCGUCUCCUCACACCCGGCCCUGUGCCCCGUCCUGGCAUCCCUUGGCCCCUUGUCGCCUUCUGCUCGGUGCCUCCCGGUUGUCCAACCCCGCCCCCGAGCGCGGAGCCCCGGGUCUGGCCCGUCCGGCCCCUGCUCCCACGCCCCUUCCCCCAUCGCCGGCAUUUCCCGGGCUCGGCUUCGCCCCGGCCGCCGGGGCCUCUCCCCUCUGCCCUUUCUCUCCCUUCUCGCAGCCCUGGGACCACGUCCUAGCCCCGCAGUCCCCUGGGAUGAGACCCUCGUCUCGCCGGGAUCGGACAUUUGCCCCCACGUCUACCCCGGCUGCGCUUCUUGAGCUCAUCGCCCCAUCAUCCUACCCGUUAUGUUGGUUAUCUUUCUGAAGUAGACUGUCCAUGGCCUGAACAUUUUCCGAAAAUCAUUUUGAGCAAAAUAUCUGUUUAAUAACAAGAUAACCACAUCAAGAUGGUUGGAAAGCUGAAGCAGAACUUACUAUUGGCAUGUCUGGUGAUUAGUUCUGUGACUGUGUUUUACCUGGGCCAGCAUGCCAUGGAAUGCCAUCACCGGAUAGAGGAACGUAGCCAGCCAGUCAAAUUGGAGAGCACAAGGACCACUGUGAGAACUGGCCUGGACCUCAAAGCCAACAAAACCUUUGCCUAUCACAAAGAUAUGCCUUUAAUAUUUAUUGGAGGUGUGCCUCGGAGUGGAACCACACUCAUGAGGGCCAUGCUGGACGCACAUCCUGACAUUCGCUGUGGAGAGGAAACCAGGGUCAUUCCCCGAAUCCUGGCCCUGAAGCAGAUGUGGUCACGGUCAAGUAAAGAGAAGAUCCGCCUGGAUGAGGCUGGUGUUACUGAUGAAGUGCUGGAUUCUGCCAUGCAAGCCUUCUUACUAGAAAUUAUCGUUAAGCAUGGGGAGCCAGCCCCUUAUUUAUGUAAUAAAGAUCCUUUUGCCCUGAAAUCUUUAACUUACCUUUCUAGGUUAUUCCCCAAUGCCAAAUUUCUCCUGAUGGUCCGAGAUGGCCGGGCAUCAGUACAUUCAAUGAUUUCUCGAAAAGUUACUAUAGCUGGAUUUGAUCUGAACAGCUAUAGGGACUGUUUGACAAAGUGGAAUCGUGCUAUAGAGACCAUGUAUAACCAGUGUAUGGAGGUUGGUUAUAAAAAGUGCAUGUUGGUUCACUAUGAACAACUUGUCUUACAUCCUGAACGGUGGAUGAGAACACUCUUAAAGUUCCUCCAGAUUCCAUGGAACCACUCAGUAUUGCACCAUGAAGAGAUGAUUGGGAAAGCUGGGGGAGUGUCUCUGUCAAAAGUGGAGAGAUCUACAGACCAAGUAAUCAAGCCAGUCAAUGUAGGAGCUCUAUCAAAAUGGGUUGGGAAGAUACCGCCAGAUGUUUUACAAGACAUGGCAGUGAUUGCUCCUAUGCUUGCCAAGCUUGGAUAUGACCCAUAUGCCAACCCACCUAACUACGGAAAACCUGAUCCCAAAAUUAUUGAAAACACUCGAAGGGUCUAUAAGGGAGAAUUCCAACUACCUGACUUUCUUAAAGAAAAACCACAGACUGAGCAAGUGGAGUAGCAGAACCAGGAGCCUCUUCCAUACAUGAGGUAAUCUCCCUGCCCGCCCCACCAAACACACACAAGGCCUCAUUUCUUUACCAGCGUGUUGUAGGAUGGACCGCAUCAGCAGUUGCCUCUGCAGCAUUUCACCCUGGCUUGUGUGUGGAGGUUGGGAGGGGCCAACCUGUGCUGAGGAGGACUCAGGAGAACUGGGGACACAGCAAAGCCCUUAGGAUGGAUACUAUCUUUCUUAUCUUUUGGGUCCCUUUGGCAUUUCAAUAACAGUAUCUGUGUUCUCUGGAGCUUCCUUUAAAGAACCUUAGGAUCCAUUUCUUCACGUGAGGAGGAAUCAGGGUGCUGACCCCUGGACACUUAAAGAACCUUAGGACCCAUUUCUUCACAUGAGGAGGAAUCAGGGUGCUGACCCCUGGGACACUUAAAGAACCUUAGGACCCAUUUCUUCACAUGAGGAGGAAUCAGGGUCUUGACCCCUGGACACUUAACCUUAGGACCCAUUUCUUCACAUGAGGAGGAAUCAGGGUGCUGCCCCCUGGACACUUAAAGAACCUUAGGACCCAUUUCUUCACAUGAGGAAUCAGGGUGCUGCCCCCUGGACACUUAAAGAACCUUAGGACCCAUUUCUUCACAUGAGGAGGAAUCAGGGUGCUGCCCCCUGGACACUUGAAGAACCUUAGGACCCAUUUCUUCACAUAAGGAGGAAUCAGGGUCUUGACCCCUGGACACUUUAAGAACCUUAGGACCCAUUUCUUCACACGAGGAAUCAUGGUGCUGACCCCUGGACAUCUGGUGCCCCUGACAGUGCCCCCACAGUAGCAACAAUAGCAGAUGACAGUCAGUUAUUUAGAAAUGGGCAGGAGCAGCCCUGGUUUUGGCCAUCUGCUUGCUUUGCACCCAGCAGCUACUUGCAUGCAUCUGAAAGCACCAGAGUGAGGGUGUGUGUGCCUCCCAGGCAGUCUUCCUGAGGCAGCUGUUCUCAACAUCCAUCCUCCUGGCCCCUGAUCUGCAGGAACCUCCCCAACCGCCUGGCUUGUCUAGGCCUGUAGCUGGGAAGGAAGAGACGAAGACACAGGGAGAACACACCGGGACUCCACACCUGUAACCACAUUCUGUUUGUUCGCCCUAGGAAAGAUUGCUGCCUUUUCAGCAGAAGGGAAAUUCCUAGGAUUGGCUGUCCCCUGCCAAGCUUGGUGGAGCGUCUGCACCUUGGCUGCGCCGCCUGUGCAUUUGCCAGUUUCCUCCCACUGAGAGGAUGGAGGUGUCCGCACAGCUUUGGGCCUCGUGAGGGAUCUGCCUCCUGAGCAAAGAGCUCUUGAUCCCGAUUUCAUGCACAGCCCUGCAGUAAGGAGCCCAGAAGGAACAUGUGUUUCCUGUUAAAACUCCUCUUGUUCUCUUUUCUUACAUUAUGACGUUUGUUUUCAAGGAGAGGGUUUAAAAAUGGGAUCCUGUAAGCAGACUUGGGCAGUCUCCUUUUGAAAUAGGUUGUCUGUACAUGUUCUAAUGUUUUGUAGAACACGUGUGCCUGUUUAAGUGUAUUGAUGUGAAUAAUAUUAAAUAUCCUAAUUAUUUAAUUCAUUGUAUUGUUUCUGAGAAGUUGGGAAAUUACCAUUAUACAUUUACAACCUAAUGACUUUUGUAUUUUAUUUUUCAAAAUAAAAGCUUUCAAUGUGAAGCA